AUCUGAGUCUUCUGAAUCCCACUUAGAACUGUGUUGAGCUCUCACCCAUCACGAUGAGCAACAAAUUCCUGGGCACCUGGAAACUUGUCUCUAGUGAGAACUUUGACGAUUACAUGAAAGCUCUGGGUGUGGGGUUAGCCACCAGAAAACUGGGAAAUUUGGCCAAACCCACUGUGAUCAUCAGCAAGAAAGGAGAUAUUAUAACUAUACGAACUGAAAGUACCUUUAAAAAUACAGAAAUCUCCUUCAAGCUAGGCCAGGAAUUUGAAGAAACCACAGCUGACAAUAGAAAGACCAAGAGCAUCGUAACCCUGCAGAGAGGAUCACUGAAUCAAGUGCAGAGAUGGGAUGGCAAAGAGACAACCAUAAAGAGAAAGCUAGUGAAUGGGAAAAUGGUAGCGGAAUGUAAAAUGAAGGGCGUGGUGUGCACCAGAAUCUAUGAGAAGGUCUGAAAAAUCAUUUCUUCAUUGAAGUGGCUUUUUAUCAUUUAAUGAUGGAAAUCAAUUGCUUCCAUUGACAAAACUGAAUACACUGCAAAUAUUUGUUUUUGCUUUUGUCUUAAUAUAUCAGAUAUGCAAAGGCCUAAACUGAGAAUUAAUCUAAAAGUCAGUGUUAUUUAAACAUUUUCAAUGUGCAUGCAUGUCAUUAUUACAUCAAAGCAUAUAUAUUGGCCAGACACAAACAGUUGAUGAUGUCAUUCAAUUAACUACAAAAUUCUAAUCUAUGUUGAACUUUGUAUACUUGAAAUGAUAAUAAAAAGGAUAUAAUUUCUUAGUAAAAUGAAAUCAAAGUAUUGAUCAGGGUAGCAAACUCAAAUGCUGACAGGGGCCAGAGGAGAUAUGGGGAAGGAGCAUCAGAAAUGAGGCAAGCUAGGAGAAUGGGCUAUUAUAAUGUAAAGAAUUGUAGUCUCAGUUAAAAGGGGUAGCCUCUACUCCAGCCAACAUUUUAAAAUUAAUGGAUAAUUUAUAGACAGUUAAAUUUAUAGACAGUUAAGUAAAAAUGGAUAAUUUAUAGACAGAUAAUUUAUAGACAGGUAAAUGUGAGUUAAAUAUAACUCACAUCCCACUCAAGACACAAAACAUUUUCUUAAUCCUAGUACAUUUUUUUCUGUCCCUUCCCAAUCAGUGUCCUUUUCUGUUCCACCCCUACCAAAAGCAAGUAGUGGUUUGGUUUCUAUCAUAUAGAUUAAUUUUACCUGCUCAUAUGAAGGGAAUUGUACAUCAUGCAUUCUUUUCUGUUUGCCUUUUUUAAAUUCAGCAUCAUGUUUUUGUGAUACAUCCACAUUGUUGCAUGCAGCUGUAGUUUGUUUCUUUUUAUUACCAAGUACUAUUUCAUUGUAUGAAUAUAUCACAGUUUAUCCAUUCUACUAUUAAGACAAUUGAGCUAUUUCUAAUUUUCGGCUGCUAUGAAUAAAGCUGCUACAAAUAUUUUUGUACAAGACUUUUUGUAAACAUAGGAGUCCCUUUAUUUUAAAUAAAUAACUAGUCAUAUCAUUAGGUCCAGUAAUUGUUGACAGGCAGGAACGGGGGACCAUUGCAUUGUGCCCAAGUAAUAAUAAAACUAUUUCAGAUGUAUUAUAUGAUUGAGCAAAUGAGAAAACAUGUUGAUGUUGAUGGGAGUCAGGAUGUUCACUAUGGAAAAACAAAUAUACAAAUAUGAAAUGAGGGAAGGCAAGAAAGAACCAUGUGGAAAUGGAAUAGAAUUGGUAUAAAUUCAUAAUUUCUAAACCAUGUAUAUGUACGUUUAUAUGUAUUAUAAUUGCAUACACAUGCCUCCAUGCAUAUAUGUGUGUGAUAAUACACAUGCAUUUAUGUGCGUGUGUGUAUACACAUGCAUAUAUUUACUAAUCCUAUCUGCCAAAAUGGCUUAGACACAAAAACACCUCAGCAGAAAUGAAUAUACCUAGCACUCAGAUCUUCGUGUCUAAUAUAGUUUGCCACUAAAAGGAACCAAGGCUACUUGGAAAAAUGGAUGAUUCCAAAGCAAGGGCAAGGUAGGAACAAGAUGAGCUUGAAAUAUCUUGUUAUGCCAGAAAGUAAUGUUAAAAAAAAAAAUAGAGGUAUAUUGCCAAAACAUAGAGCCAGCUUGAAGGGGCUCCCACUGGCCAAACUUGAGCCAAUCUGAGAGCAAAAUAAUUGAGAAAAAUAAAUAACAAGAUAAUUGAGAAAAAAAUAAAAUAAAUUCCCAAUUCCAUUGGGAAAAAAUAGAAAUCCAUGAAUCCAUACUGAUAUAAUGAUAGAUAAUCGAUAGAUAGGUAGAUGACUGACAGAUGAUAGAUAGAUAUAUAGAUAGAUAGAUAGAUAGAUAGAUAGAUAGAUAGAUAGAUAGAGAAAUGAGAAGGUUUCUCUUUUGCAAUAGAACGUCAUGGACCAGUGUUAAAUGUGAGUGGAAGGAGUUCUGGAAUUGGAAAACCAUCAUUUUUCAACCAUCACAGUAAAUAUGGCUCAGGCAAGAAUUAUCAAUCAAUGCUAAAGCUAGGGGGAAAUUUCGCUUAGGAGCAGGAUAUUAGGGUAUUAGUCUGGGCUUAAAGUAUCUCCUCACAGAUUGUUGUUAGUUUCUGGGGAAAGAAUAGUAACCAUGCAAUGGAAAAAAAUGGACAACCUCUUGACUAGGUUAUCAAAAUUAACCUCACCAAUAAAGGGUGGAUGUUCAACAUGUGCCUUCAAAUGUGACCCACUGAGAAGGAAACAACAUCACUGUAACAACAACAACCAGAAACGACAGGGGGUUUUGACUGAAUUCUUCAAAAAUGUCAAUGUCAUAGAAGACAAAGAAAGGUUGUGGAAAUGUUUCAGAUUAAAUGAUAGUAAAAACACCUGACAACUAAACAUAGUAAGUAAUACUAGACUGGAUUCUGUACCAGAGGUAACAUAAGUGCUCCAAAGGACAAUGUUAGGUCAACUGGCAAAUUGGAAUAUAGACAGUCAAUCAGAUAAGAAGUAUACUUUGAUUAAGUAAAAAAAAUCCCUAUUCUUGGAAAAUACACAAUAAAGUAUUUUGAGGUAAAGGGCCAUAAUGUAUGCAAUCUACUCUCAAAAAAUUCAGAAACAUAUAUUUGUGUGCAUUUGCAUGUGCAACAGUACACACAAACAUACAUAAAGAGAGCAAUUGAUAAGGCAAAUAAGGUAACAUUUAACAAUAAUCUGAUACACAUAAAUAGAGAAAGAGCAAUUGAUAAAGUAAAUGAGGUAAAAUUUAACAAUAAUCUGAGCAAAAGGUAUAUGUGUUUUCUUUGAGACAGUCUGAUUCUUGCAACUUAUUCUGUAAGUUGGAACUUAUUUCCAAACAUGAUUGAAAAAAAACCCCGCACUUGGCAACUUCUUCUCUUUUUCAGCCUAGAAAUGUCUGUGUUAAGUGGUUUUUUAUUUAUUGUUGUUGUUUGUUGUUAUUGUUGUUUUGUUGCCAGGCUCCAACUCACAAAAUACGAGUUUAAAAACUGCGUUGUUAUUUUUAGAGAUUUGUGAUAAUACAACUUGUUAUAAAAUUUAUUCCUCAAUAAAUAUAAUUUCUCUACUAUGCAAAAA